AUUCCACGCGGCUCGAGCCCGCGUGCGGGCCUCUUUCAGGCCGCUCCUAGUGGACGCAGAGGCGGGCCGAGGACGGUGCCAGCCCCCAGGCCCCAAGAGGAGCUGGUCCCCAGGACAGAGGAGGGAGAGGAGCAAGAGGCUCCCCUGGGCCCCUUCCAGGCCCCACCUCCAGGUCACAGGCGCGAGAUGGAGUCCCCAAGAGGGUGGACCCUGCAGGUGGCCCCAGAGGAAGGCCAGGUCCUCUGCAAUGUGAAGACUGCCACGAGGGGCCUCUCUGAGGGGGCUGUGUCUGGAGGCUGGGGGGCCUGGGAAAACUCCACGGAGGUUCCGAGGGAGGCAGGGGACGGCCAGCGGCAGCAAGCCACACUGGGGGCGGCGGACGAACAGGGAGGCCCCGGCAGGGAGCUGGGCCCCGCAGACGGUGGGCGGGACGGGGCUGGGCCCAGGAGCGAGCCUGCAGACCGGGCGUUGCGCCCUUCGCCUCUCCCAGAGGAGCCGGGCUGCCGGUGCGGGGAGUGCGGCAAGGCGUUCAGCCAGGGCUCUUACUUGCUGCAGCAUCGGCGCGUGCACACAGGCGAGAAGCCGUACACGUGCCCCGAGUGCGGCAAGGCCUUCGCCUGGAGCUCCAACCUCAGCCAGCACCAGCGCAUCCACAGCGGCGAGAAGCCCUACGCUUGCAGGGAGUGCGGCAAGGCCUUCCGCGCGCACUCGCAGCUCAUCCACCACCAGGAGACACACAGCGGCCUGAAGCCCUUCCGCUGCCCGGACUGCGGCAAGUCCUUCGGCCGAAGCACCACGCUGGUGCAGCACCGACGCACGCACACGGGCGAGAAGCCCUACGAGUGCCCGGAGUGCGGCAAGGCCUUCAGCUGGAACUCCAAUUUCCUGGAGCACCGGCGCGUGCACACGGGCGCGCGGCCGCACGCCUGCCGGGACUGUGGCAAGGCCUUCAGCCAGAGCUCCAACCUGGCCGAGCACCUGAAGAUCCACGCGGGCGCACGGCCACACGCCUGUCCCGACUGCGGCAAGGCCUUCGUGCGUGUGGCGGGGCUGCGGCAGCACCGGCGCACGCACAGCAGCGAGAAGCCCUUCCCCUGCGCCGAGUGCGGAAAGGCUUUCCGCGAGAGCUCGCAGCUCCUGCAGCACCAGCGCACGCACACUGGUGAGCGGCCCUUCGAGUGCGCCGAGUGCGGCCAGGCUUUCGUCAUGGGCUCCUACCUGGCGGAGCACCGGCGCGUGCACACGGGCGAGAAGCCUCAUGCGUGCGCCCAGUGCGGCAAGGCCUUCAGCCAGCGCUCCAACCUACUGAGCCACCGGCGCACGCACUCGGGCGCCAAGCCCUUCGCCUGCGCCGACUGCGGCAAGGCCUUCCGCGGCAGUUCCGGCCUGGCGCACCACCGGCUUUCGCACACGGGAGAGCGACCCUUCGCCUGCGCAGAAUGCGGCAAGGCCUUCCGCGGCAGCUCCGAGCUGCGCCAGCACCAGCGCCUGCACUCUGGCGAGAGGCCGUUCGUCUGCGCCCACUGCAGCAAGGCCUUCGUGCGCAAGUCGGAGCUCUUAAGCCACCGGCGCACGCACACGGGCGAGAGGCCCUACGCUUGCGGCGAGUGCGGGAAGCCUUUCAGCCACCGUUGCAACCUCAACGAGCACCAGAAGCGGCACGGGGGCCGCGCUGCGCCCUGACCCGAGGACGCCCUGAGCGGGAGGUCGCGGACACACGGCAUUGCGGGGUCUCGGGCGUGAGUGCGCUGUCUGCUGGCCCAGACUUUUUCGGGCCGCCGGUGCGGGCGCCCUCCUGCUGGGAGUGCAGGGGCGGCCUUGGGUGUGGAGAACCCUGGCUGCACAGUCCCUUUGACGAUAGUCCACCGGCCACCCAGGCCUGUCUGGGGACAUGUAGGAUGGGCUCUUACCCCAGGGAGGGCGGCAGGCUCCACUUCGGCGAGAGGUUCGUCCAUGCAGAGGUGGGCAAGAACUGGGGUCUCCGACAGGUGUGGCUAUUUCUUUGAGUUCUCUGGCACUGUCAAAAGCAGCCAACCCACCCCCCAGUCCACAUGGUCACCACUGCUGCUACCAGCUGCUCAGUGCAGUGGCCACUGUGUCUCCUAAGGUGCUCGCUUCAGUCAGCACUUCAUCUCAGGCAACCACAGGUGACAGUUAAACAUGAUGAAACCGCAUGCUAUGGCUUUCUAGUGUCUCAUAUUCUGUUGGCAAGAAGCUCAGCACUGCAUUCCUGACCGAGGUCAGAACCAGAUCAAUCUCAGAAUCUCACCUGUGUAGGUCUGUUUCAUGGGACUUUUCUUUUUUGGGGGAGGGGGCAGGGUUUCACUCUGUCACCCAGGCUGGAGUGCAGUGGUGCAAUCACUGUUUAUUGCAGCCGCGACUUCUUAGGCUCAGGUGAUCCUCCCACCUCAGCCUCCCAAGCAGCUGGGAUGACAGACUUGCGUCACUACACCUGGCUAAUUUUAAAAUUUUUUGUAAGGACAGUGUCUCACCAUGUUGCCUAGGCGGGUCUCAAAACUCCUGGGCUCAAGUGAUCCUCCUGCCUCAGCCUCCCAAAGCGUUGGGAUUAUAGGCGUGAGCCACCGCACCUGGCCAGGGAACCUUCUUUAUACCAAGUACCACACCAGUCAGAGUCAAGUCAGGAAAUAGAAACCACACUAGGUAUUUCAAACAGAGGGGAUAUAAGUUAGGGACUGAUUGUGCAGGUUUUGCAAGGCUCAGAGAGCAAAAGUGGAUGUUGCAGAAUCUCAGAGCUGGAUACUUGCAGGAAGCUGCUACCACCCUUAGGGCUGGAGAACCCAGGGAAGCUAAGAGGAGGGUGCAACGAGGCUGGUGUUGGGACUGCCAAAGGAAACACAGAAUGACAGCUCCAUCUCUGCAGACCUCAGAUUUGACCAGGCCUCUGGCUGCCUGGGCAGCCUCAUUGCCAAUGGGCUGAAAGGUUCUGUCACUGUUCAGUGGUCUGACUUCUGAGUUCUGUGCACACCCUGAGCUCUGCUCCUCUGGCCUGGCCACCAGUCCUUGUCUGAGUGCCCCAGGUCUGGUUAUGACUUCAGGCCUCAGCACCUGGUUGUCUCUUCUGCAAAGAAUGCAUUCUCCCCCAGUCCACCCAGAACACACAGCCUCCAUCCAGGUACUGGCUCUGAGCAGGACAGAGAGCAUGCAGCAGGUGCUCAGCAAUAUGGAAAUGGGACCAAACAGAGGGAGUCUCCACAGCUCCCCGUCCCUCACAGCAGAAGCCAGAGCCGCUGCAGUGCCCAGCUGGUCUUCAUCACGUCUAUGAGCUCUGCAAUCGCUCUGCAGUCGCCUCAACUCCUGGUCUCCUCUGCUCCUUCUCACUGCACCCGCAUCUCCCAUGUUUGCACUGGCUGUUCCCUCUGCCUGGAAUGCUCCUUGCCCAGUUAUCCCACUGUCUUCUUUGCAUCUGGCACACAGUAGAUGCUCAAUAAAUGCCUGUGGAAUGAA